CUUUUGCAGGCUCGUGGCGGUCGGUCAGCGGGGCGUUCUCCCACCUGUAGCGACUCAGGUUACUGAAAAGGCGGGAAAACGCUGCGAUGGCGGCAGCUGGGGGAGGAGGAAGAUAAGCGCGUGAGGCUGGGGUCCUGGCGCGUGGUUGGCAGAGGCAGAGACAUAAGACGUGCACGACUCGCCCCACAGGGCCCUCAGACCCCUUCCUUCCAAAGGAGCCUCCAAGCUCAUGGCCUCCUUAGGAGCGAACCCAAGGAGGACACCGCAGGGACCGAGACCUGGGGCGGCCUCCUCCGGCUUCCCCAGCCCGGCCCCAGUGCCGGGCCCCAGGGAGGCCGAGGAGGAGGAAGUCGAGGAGGAGGAGGAGCUGGCCGAGAUCCAUCUGUGUGUGCUGUGGAAUUCAGGAUACUUGGGCAUUGCCUACUAUGAUACUAGUGACUCCACUAUCCACUUCAUGCCAGAUGCCCCAGACCACGAGAGCCUCAAGCUUCUCCAGAGAGUUCUGGAUGAGAUCAAUCCCCAGUCUGUUGUUACGAGUGCCAAACAGGAUGAGAAUAUGACUCGAUUUCUGGGAAAGCUUGCCUCCCAGGAGCACAGAGAGCCUAAAAGACCUGAAAUCAUAUUUUUGCCAAGUGUGGAUUUUGGUCUGGAGAUAAGCAAACAACGCCUCCUUUCUGGAAACUACUCCUUCAUCCCAGACGCCAUGACUGCCACUGAGAAAAUCCUCUUCCUCUCUUCCAUUAUUCCCUUUGACUGCCUCCUCACAGUUCGAGCACUUGGAGGGCUGCUGAAGUUCCUGGGUCGAAGAAGAAUCGGGGUUGAACUGGAAGACUAUAAUGUCAGCGUCCCCAUCCUGGGCUUUAAGAAAUUUAUGUUGACUCAUCUGGUGAACAUAGAUCAAGACACUUACAGUGUUCUACAGAUUUUUAAGAGUGAGUCUCACCCCUCAGUGUACAAAGUGGCCAGUGGACUGAAGGAGGGGCUCAGCCUCUUUGGAAUCCUCAACAGAUGCCACUGUAAGUGGGGAGAGAAGCUGCUCAGG